AUGAGGCCUCACCCUUUGACACAGCAAGAUGAGCCCCAGGAACGGGAGGUGGGAGAAGGCAGCCUAGCCAGCCUCUACAUCCAGAGGCCCACACCCCCAGCCUUGCCAUAUGCAAUCAGGAGAGUGGGGAGAAGCCAGUCGCUGGGUCCAGGAAGCAGAAGGGAGGGUGCUGAGGGCACCUGCUGUGGGUGCUUCCUUGGGGUAGAAACGAGACCAGAAGCCCCUAGGGAUGAGAGCCUGGCCACGGCAGGGACCCUGGAAUACAGAUGGAUCCCACAUGCAGAGCGCGUCCCCGGGAGACCCCAGACCUGGACGGUCAGCAAGGCCUGGGCUCCUGCUCCCGGAAACUGCCCGGUGUGGGGGCCAGAGGGUGACCCCACAGCACUGUGGCCCAGAACACGCGAAGGCAAGCUUCACCCGACUCGGACCACUGCUACCGACCGUGGCCAGCCCACAUCACUGGAGCCCGGGCUCUUUCCCCCGACUGGGGGCAUUGCCGGGGUGUGUGCUGGGGUGCGCCCCCGUCCCCCACAGGACCUGGCCGUCCACUCCACUCACCAAGGGCAGCUCCAGCCACCCCCUGCAAGCUCUGCUGGACCCUCCCGCUCCCUCACCCAUUGCUGUAACCUUCCCGCCACCCUUGGUGCCAACCCUACACCUGGGAGCCACAAACGCCUCUUGGAUCCCAAGCCUCCAGGCAGGGUGGUUCUGAGCGGGGUAGCAUCUCCCAAGCCCUGGCCAGCCCCGAACCCCCUGCACCACCCCAGCAGGGCCCGGGGAGCUGUGGUGCUCUGAAUUCUGAGUGGCCGAUGGCGCAUCAUGCCGGUGAGAGGUAAUAAUCACUGCCUGACUCAGACACGCAGACUGCUGGGCUGUCAUGCCUAUUUCAGGAAAAUUAAUUAUACCCCAUGCCGAGAGGGAACUCGCCCAUUUAACGUCUUCAACGCACCUGCCCAGAAUGCCAUGGCACAGCCUGCCUGCACCCCUGGGCAUGGGAAAGGGUGGGCAGAGCCCCCAGUUUCUCCAGGUGUCAGGCGGGCUUGCAGGGUGGUGGCCAGCAGGGCUCCAGGCCCUUCUAGCCAGGCCCGACCCCGUCACCACUGAUACUGGAAACUGCAACCUUUGCCCAGGGAGUCCCCUUUGAAAGCCAAGCCUUUGAUCCAGCUGAGUGCCAGAAAAGGCCUUGGGCCGGCCCUGGGGCUGGCCCGAGGACCUGGCUCAGGGACCUGGCUGGCCCUACUGUGGCAUUAGAAAGCUCCGCACCAGUAAGCCGACCGUUGCCCACAUGGGAAGGCUGCCCUAUGCCCUCUGGACAGUUGGCCCUGCUGGCAAGCCCGUUUCCUUCUCCUACUUGCUCUAUGGGGCCUGCUAAGAUGGACAGCAGGCACGUCCAGGACCAGGGGCUGGGAGCUGGGCUUAGCUGCCCUGGGCUGAAAUUCAGCCCAGGCCUCUGGGCCCCGAGCUUUACCUUUCCCUGGCAAGAGUUGAUGUACACGUUGGCGUAACCAGGCUGCACACAUCCCAGGACAAGCUUCCCAACUGUGACUAGCCAUGGCUCACGUUUGCCUGGGUUCCCCCACCAGGCUCGCCCCAGGCCUGCCCUUGCUAUGUCCUCAGACACCCGGGGGCAGGCACAGCUGUCACCCUCCUGGCAGCUGGAAAAGAAGGGCUUGAGCAGUUCUACAGCUCAGCGAGGCUGCAGGGCUUUGCAGGGAAGAGCCGCCAGGUGCCAGACGUCACGCGUGGCAAGGCAAAUCCUACAGCCGGAACUGGCUGGCUCCGGUGCAGGCUUGGGACUUGUAGGCACACAGAUCCACCCCGUCCUAGAGAAGCUGUCAUUGCCACAUCUACCAAUUGAGGCUGUUGCAUUUGUUAGUAGUUUUCAAAUGUGUUUUGUCAUUGUUAUCAUAAAAAUAAAUUUUAUAAGAACACCAUUCCACCAAACACAGUAAGAGUGAUGGUUUCAGGCAAGCCCACAGCCUCCCUAAUGCUUGCUGUGGCCCGGCGUCUACCAUCUGACCACGAAGACGUGGACAGAGGCGUGUGCACCCCAUCCCCUUCCCACGUAGAGAUACAAUGGGUAAUUAACGCACAGUUGACCCAGGAGAUGACAUGAAAAGAGGACAUUCCCAGGAACAAAGAGGAGACCAGACAAACCAACUGGACACAGAGCAAGAAACACAGGCAUGUCAUUCACUACACUCAAUACUACAUGGG